AGGCGUGCAGCAUUCGCCAUGCUCCGCUCACGCGUGGGAGACUGGGCUGUGGGGUACCGGCCCGGAAAGCACGCAGCCUCCAAAGCCGCCUUCCUCAGGGAAAUUUGCGUGACCUUACUGCCCUCCGUCUACAGGCCUUGUACCUCUCCAGGCCGAUUUUUCCACAAUUUAAAUCUCAGUUCACCUGGUAUCCAGCUCCAGCAACUUAGAGCGUUUCACGUCACGCCGGGCGCCAGGCGUCGGCUUGUAUAACCUGAAAACGCUCCUGUUUUUCUCAUCUGUGCAGUGGGUAUGAUUUUUUUUUCAUCAACAAAUUUCACGUGGGUAAUCUGAAAUGAAACCACUUAAGUUAUGAAACUCUUUCCUUUUGAGUUAUUCUGGAGACCUUACUCCGCCUUCGGAACCGCCCCAGUGGUGUCACAUACUUGAGGGCCUGACUCUCGGUUGCCAGACAUGGCACAGAAUGUUCGAUUUUACUACCAGCUCUCACACUCCGCUUCUGUUUCCCCUUCUCUUACGGGCCGCUGCUCAAACCUUUAUUUAUCAAAUUUAAGUGAGUUCAGGUUUUGAUUCCCACCAUGGCCAUCACCCAGUUUCGGUUAUUUAAAUUUUGUACCUGCCUAGCAACAGUAUUCUCAUUCCUAAAGAGAUUAAUAUGCAGAUCUGGCAGAGGACGGAAAUUAAGUGGAGACCAAAUAACUUUGCCAACUACAGUUGAUUAUUCAUCAGUUCCUAAGCAGACAGAUGUUGAAGAGUGGACUUCCUGGGAUGAAGAUGCACCCACCAGUGUAAAGAUCGAAGGAGGGAAUGGGAAUGUGGCAACACAACAAAAUUCUUUGGAACAACUGGAACCUGACUAUUUUAAGGACAUGACACCAACUAUUAGGAAAACUCAGAAAAUUGUUAUUAAGAAGAGAGAACCAUUGAAUUUUGGCAUCCCAGAUGGGAGCACAGGUUUCUCUAGUAGAUUAGCAGCUACACAAGAUCUGCCUUUUAUUCAUCAGUCUUCUGAAUUAGGUGACUUAGAUACCUGGCAGGAAAAUACCAAUGCAUGGGAAGAAGAAGAAGAUGCAGCCUGGCAAGCAGAAGAAGUUCUGAGACAGCAGAAACUAGCAGACAGAGAAAAGAGAGCAGCCGAACAACAAAGGAAGAAAAUGGAAAAGGAAGCACAACGGCUAAUGAAGAAGGAACAAAACAAAAUUGGUGUGAAACUUUCAUAACACAUGUUCAAAUUUUAUCAUGCCAGUAGGAGAAAUCUCAGCUCCACAACCCAAGCAACAUUUGUAUGGAUUUAAGAGUAUUUUAAGAAGACAUACUGCUUGAUUUUAAUACAUUGAUCAGGCCAUCCAGGACACCACGAUUCUCCCAAAGUACCUUGAACUCUUAGUGAUUGAGACUCAAAAAAACAAAAAAGACUUGAGACAAUGUUUUCUUCAACAUGCUCCAAAUAUAAGACAUUUGUUUGCUGUACAGAAAGUAUCACAAAUGGAAUAUAUCAGUACCUCUCAAGCUAGUGUUUCUAGCUAAAUAAAUGGGUGUAUAUAAUUUUAUGGUGGAAAAGAACUGUACUGUCUGUUAUGAUUUCCUUCAAUGUGCAUAAUGAUAAAAUAAAUAAUUUUAAUAUUCUUUUGUUUCCAUGGUUACCUGACCUAAAUUAGAUAAAUUGUAGGGCUUUAGCUUUCUUAUUUUUGUCAAAAGUUGGUGUUGACAUACAUUCCCUCUAAUUUGAACUGGUAUUGUUUACGUUUGAUACAACAUUAAGGAAUUUGAUGAUUUUCAUUUCAUGAAAAUGACAUUAAAUGCAAUAAUUUUACUUAUCAUAAACAUUUUGUACAUCAUUAUUUUCUUUUGGAUUAGUGUUGUCAUACAUGUAAUUUAUAUCACAUGUAUAAACAUUGAAAAUCAACUAAAAUGACAUUUGUUCUACAUUAUAACUUGUGAGUUUCAAGAACUAGUAUUAGUAGUUUUUUCCUUUCAUUAUAGAUUGUAAGAUGUUGUGGUAUCUUUGAGUGCCUUAGUUCUUCCUUCCUCCCAAAAGCCAUUAAUUUACAAAUGCUUAAAGCCAUCAGGUCAAAUAUUUCAAAGCCUUUAGAUGAUUUCUGUACUAGCUUUAGAUGUCUGACGUUAUGUAGGUUACCUGUGUUCUUGGCUAGGAAAACAUUAUUGAUUCAUUAAAUCAUAAAGGUGGGAAUAAUAAUCUUUUAUUUAUGAUGUUGAUUGGCUCCAAAAUAGUCUUAAGGAAAUAAAUACUGGGUCUGUAGGGGAAAAGUAGACUUCAUAGUUUAAAAUCCCAUUAACCUUUUCACCGCAGUUGAAAUGCAUCCAGCCUGAUUUUCCUAUCAUUUUGGAAUUUUUAAGGAUUUUUACUUUCUUAAGUUACUGCCUAGAAUCAACAUUCGGUGAGAUUUUGAAAUGUCAUAGAUACUGUACAGGCCAAACCUUACUAAUUUAUUUUACUUAAAGUGAUAUUUUAUAGAAAAAUCAUAAGUUAUACAAUGAGAACCCUUUAAGCCCUUAGCCUAAGCUUUCAGACUAAAUGUGAUUAUAGAAUAAGAUGAAAGUUAACUUUGGUACAGAGCUUUUUAUAGCCCCAAAUUAUAUUUCCAGUUAUUAUAUUCAUUAGAAUUUCUGCUAAUAAACUCCCAACUUAAAUAGAA